AAGUUGGAGCGCGCCCCGCCCGGCGCCCUCGCCGUCCCCGCGCCCUCCCCGCCGGGGCGCGCUGCCCGCAGCUCCACGCGCGCCAGGGCCGCCCUGGGGAGGGCGCGCGCGCGAGCGGCGACCGGAGAGGAGCUCGGGGCGGCGGAGGUGAUGACGGCGGCGGCAUGGAGUUCCCUGAGCACGGCGGACGGCUGCUGGGCCGCCUGAGACAGCAGCGCGAGCUGGGCUUCCUAUGCGACUGCACCGUGCUGGUGGGCGACGCGCGCUUCCCGGCCCACCGUGCCGUGCUGGCCGCGUGCAGCGUCUACUUCCAUCUCUUCUACAGGGACCGGCCCGCGGGCAGUCGCGACACGGUGCGGCUCAACGGCGACAUCGUCACGGCGCCCGCCUUCGGCCGCCUACUGGACUUCAUGUACGAGGGCCGCCUGGACCUGCGCAGCCUGCCUGUGGAGGACGUCCUGGCAGCCGCCAGCUACCUGCACAUGUAUGACAUCGUCAAGGUCUGCAAGGGCAGGCUCCAGGAGAAGGAUCGAAGUCUGGACCCGGGGAACCCUGCCCCUGGGGCAGAACCUGCUCAGCCACCGUGCCCCUGGCCUGUCUGGACCGCGGACCUCUGCCCAGCUGCCCGAAAGGCCAAGCUCCCCCCGUUUGGGGUCAAGGCUGCCCUCCCUCCUCGAGCAUCUGGGCCUCCUCCCUGCCAGGUCCCAGAAGAGUCAGACCAGGCCCUGGACCUGUCGUUGAAGUCUGGCCCAAGGCAGGAGCGGGUCCACCCACCGUGCGUCCUCCAGACACCCCUCUGCAGCCAGAGGCAGCCAGGGGCCCAGCCACUGGUGAAGGACGAACGGGACUCACUGUCCGAACAGGAGGAGAGCAGCAGCUCUAGGAGCCCCCACAGUCCCCCGAAGCCACCUCCUGUUCCUGCAGCCAAGGGCCUGGUGGUGGGCUUGCAGCCGCUGCCCCUCAGCGGAGAGGGCAGCCGGGAGCUGGAGCUUGGUGCAGGGCGACUGGCGAGUGAGGACGAGCUGGGGCCUGGUGGGCCCCUCUGCAUCUGCCCGUUGUGCAGCAAGCUGUUUCCCAGCUCCCACGUGCUGCAGCUGCACCUCAGUGCCCACUUCCGUGAGCGAGACAGCACCCGGGCCCGGCUCUCACCCGACGGCGUGGCACCCACCUGCCCGCUCUGUGGGAAGACCUUCUCGUGCACAUACACACUGAAGAGGCACGAGCGGACACACUCGGGUGAGAAGCCCUAUACGUGUGUGCAGUGUGGCAAAAGUUUUCAGUACUCCCACAACCUGAGCCGGCACACCGUAGUGCACACUCGAGAGAAGCCGCAUGCCUGCCGGUGGUGUGAGCGCCGUUUCACGCAGUCCGGGGACCUCUACCGCCACGUCCGCAAGUUUCACUGUGGCCUCGUCAAGUCCCUUCUGGUGUGAUGCAUCCCUGUGGGUCCUGAGGGUGGGGUGGAAGGGAAGGGAUGGGCCCUCCCAGGUGGGACACAGCAUGGGGUGUGAAGCCUGACCAGGUGGAGGUCCCUGCUUGGGCCAGAUGGCUCCACCCUCCUGGCAGAGAGAAUGCUGCCUCUUCCUGGAACUUGGCCUCAGACUCGGUAACUUGGGCAGCCUUCCUCCCACCUUGCCUCUCCUUUCCCCUCACUCUCCAACUCAUUCCGGCCCCCAGGCUGUGCCCUGCCUAGGCUGUGACACUAUCUUCCUCUCCCGUCCCCUCCAGCCAAGUUCUGAGGGGUGUCCAACCAGCACCUGGCUCUGCCCCCGUUUCUCCGUGUGAGAUGGCACAUCCAUCUCCCGGCCCGGGACUUUCCUGACCACCUCUCUGGCAGGCUUGGGGAGGUCUUCAUGAGCCUGGCCCCACGCUAGGUGAAUUAUUCACAUGUCAGAAAAGUUGUUGGUGUGCGUCCCAAUGGGGCGCUGGGAGGGAACAGGACACUCCUGGGGAGCGGCAGCAGGAACCCCUGCCAGGAAGGCCUGGGGCACAGUGAGUGCCAGCAGGGGCCAUCUGGGCACAGCUGGUGUCUCGGGGUGGGGGGGGGGGUGCAGCCCCAGCAGGGAUCCUAAGGCAGCAGGAGUAGAGCCAGCUAGAAGCUGAGUGGCUGUGGCAUCAUUGUCACUCGGGUGGGACGUGGGUCCAUGAGAGCGUGCAAUUAUGACCACACUGUAACUUUGAGCAGAGAAAGUGGGAAUUUGGAACUGGAUUCUCUUUAGAGCCAGGAAGAGCCUCCUGAGGCGGCCAGAUGUCUGCUGGUGGCCGCCCAGCCACAUGCUUGUCUGCCUGAGUGCAGGUCUAGGAAGCCUCUGGGCAUCCCCCAGGGUGGGGUCUGGGCCGCUGAGCUGUGUGCUGCUGCUGGGCCACCGUGGGCCUUACCUUGACGGUCACUCUGCCUGCUAGGGGGUUUCCCUGGAGCUGUGGGCAUUUCCGUGCACUGACUGAGCAGAGGCAAGGGCUGCCCUGUCCGCCAGGGGCAGGGUUUGCGGGCCUUCCUUUCCCCACGGCGAGGCAUGGGUGAAAGUGGCCAUGGCGGCAGGGUUAGGGGCAGGUGAGGAGUGGGAGUCGCAGCACCCUAGGGGCCUCCAUCCGCAGCCUUGGGAGACUGACGCUCCUCGAACAUGAAUAGAAUGUGGAGACCACAACCCCCACACAUGUCGUUGGUUCAGGUCGCCCUGCUUUGCCUGCCUAAUGGAGCACAUCUUGCUGCCAGAACCUCACUGGCCUCUGGGGGUCGGCAGGUGCAGAGCCACCUGGACGCCUGGAGACCACCUGGGAUGUUUCCUCUGUGACUGGGAAUGGCCUUGACAACAGAGUCCAGCCAAGUCUACGUUAUUUUCUCAUCUCCUGACAACACUGGAUGUCAUAUUUAUUAGUCAGCCUGGUCUGGAGUGAAAGACCGUCCCUAGCGCAUCUCCCACGCGCCCUGGGCUCCUGGUGUGCUGGGUGCCAGCCUGGGAGCCCAGCGCUUCUGGGUGAUGCCCCAGGGCUCAGAGGCCCUGGAUGGCUUUGGUCUCGAGACAGCUGGGGGAGGGGCCCUGCUUCUGAUUGUCCUGGGCCCCAGCCCCCACCUCUGCAAGGGAUCGGUGUGAUGUGCUCCAUAAUCGGGUGGGGGGUGUGUGUGUGUGUGUGUGUGUGUGUAUGUAUGCAUGCGUCUGGCACAUGGCAAGGCCCAAGCCAACCCGGCACCCCGUAGAUGGGCAGCUACACUGCCACCCAAGCACGGAGAUGUGGCCGCGGCACUGGGUCCCCCAGUGGGUCCCAUGGGGGAAGAACUUCCCUUUGCUGGGGUGGGCAGCCUGCCCUGAGCUAUCAACACUGGAUUUGUUGUCUUCUGCACAGCUACUGUGAAGAUAACGUAAGGAGAAGUGGUCAGUUUUCAUUUUAUAACUGACACAGUUGGGACAAAAUAUAUACGUGUACAUAUAUUUAAGACACUAAUUGUGUGGGAGAGUUUAGUAGAGGCCUGUGCAGACACAAGGCAAACAGCGUCAGCAGCGUGGGGGUCUCCUGGGCCAGCUCGGCACCUGUGGGUGCUCUGACCCUGGGGGUGGGGACAGCUCCGUGCUAACCCCAGCAGACAGUUGUUGGUGCACAGUGUCUAGGAGGCGUGGGAAUGGGUGCUGUCUUCCUCUUUUCACAUCAUGGCGACAGUAAUAAAGCCCACCUCCAGUGGAAA